CUCUUCGGCGUCUGGCCCGGCGCUCGCGGACAGGCGCCCGCGUUGGGGGCCGGGGGAUUGAGGUGUCCGGUCCUCCCGGGACACAUUCACACACAAGCGCAGCCGCCAGAAAGCUGCCGAGGACCAGGCCGGCGCCCAGGGUCGUGGGCGCCAGUGCGGAUUUCGAUUCUGAGAUUCACCCUUUCUUCCCCGCCCUAACGCUGUGCUUCUCUGGCGCCCUCCCGGCGCCCGGGCUGCUUUGGGCCGCUAGGCACUCAGCUUCCAGCCGGGUUCGUCGGCCUCAGGGCGGAAAGAGAUGGCCACAGCCGCGCGCCCGCAGCCUGGGAGUCCUGAGCUGGGGCCAGGAGCCCCGGGCCGCGGCGAGCUCACUUUCAGCAGCAGGGCUGGCACCUGGAGAAGAACAGCCUCUCCCCGCUGCCGUCCGGAGUACCACUCAUCAUCCGCGCCAGGUCUCAGGACGUCCAGGCUGCCCUCUUUCCAGCGGGGCGGGAGAGGGUGCAUCCGAGGGUCUCACUCGGAAUACAGAGUCCACGCGUAUCUGGUGCAGGCCGUGAGAGCAGCGGGCAAGUGCGAUGCGGUCUUCAAGGGCUUUUCGGACUGUUUGCUCAAGCUGGGCGACAGCAUGGCCAACUACCCGCAGGGCCUGGACGACAAGACGAACAUCAAGACCGUGUGCACAUACUGGGAGGAUUUCCACAGCUGCACGGUCACAGCCCUUACGGAUUGCCAGGAAGGGGCGAAAGAUAUGUGGGAUAAACUGAGAAAAGAAUCCAAAAACCUCAACAUCCAAGGCAGCUUAUUCGAACUCUGCGGCAGCGGCAACGGGGCGGCGGGGUCCCUGCUCCCGGCGUUCCCGGUGCUCCUGGUGUCUCUCUCGGCAGCUUUAGCGACCUGGCUUUCCUUCUGAGCGUGGGGCCAGCUCCCCCCGCGCGCCCACCCACACUCACUCCAUGCUCCCGGAAAUCGAGAGGAAGAUCCAUUAGUUCUUUGGGGACGUUGUGAUUCUCUGUGAUGCUGAAAACACUCAUAUAGGAUUGUGGGAAAUCCUGAUUCUCUUUUUUAUUUCGUUUGAUUUCUUGUGUUUUAUUUGCCAAAUGUUACCAAUCAGUGAGCAAGCAAGCACAGCCAAAAUCGGACCUCAGCUUUAGUCCGUCUUCACACACAAAUAAGAAAACGGCAAACCCACCCCAUUUUUUAAUUUUAUUAUUAUUAAUUUUUUUUGUUGGCAAAAGAAUCUCAGGAACGGCCCUGGGCCACCUACUAUAUUAAUCAUGCUAGUAACAUGAAAAAUGAUGGGCUCCUCCUAAUAGGAAGGCGAGGAGAGGAGAAGGCCAGGGGAAUGAAUUCAAGAGAGAUGUCCACGGACGAAACAUACGGUGAAUAAUUCACGCUCACGUCGUUCUUCCACAGUAUCUUGUUUUGAUCAUUUCCACUGCACAUUUCUCCUCAAGAAAAGCGAAAGGACAGACUGUUGGCUUUGUGUUUGGAGGAUAGGAGGGAGAGAGGGAAGGGGCUGAGGAAAUCUCUGGGGUAAGAGUAAAGGCUUCCAGAAGACAUGCUGCUAUGGUCACUGAGGGGUUAGCUUUAUCUGCUGUUGUUGAUGCAUCCGUCCAAGUUCACUGCCUUUAUUUUCCCUCCUCCCUCUUGUUUUAGCUGUUACACACACAGUAAUACCUGAAUAUCCAACGGUAUAGAUCACAAGGGGGGGAUGUUAAAUGUUAAUCUAAAAUAUAGCUAAAAAAAGAUUUUGACAUAAAAGAGCCUUGAUUUUAAAAAAAAAAGAGAGAGAGAUGUAAUUUAAAAAGUUUAUUAUAAAUUAAAUUCAGCAAAAAAAGAUUUGCUACAAAGUAUAGAGAAGUAUAAAAUAAAAGUUAUUGUUUGAAA